AGUUUCUCCUUUGUUUUACGUUUGGGAGGAGGUGGCAUUGGAAAUAGCAGAGUGCUUCGCGGUAACAGGGGUUGGAGUGCAAUGGUGUGAUCUCAGCUCACUGCAACCCCUGCCUCCCAGGCUCCAGCGAUCCUCCCACCUCAGCCUCCUGAAUAGCUGACCACCAGCACACUAGGCAAACCCACCCCACUCACGGCCUCCCUUGGGAAUUCAGACCUAACCAUCGCUGAGCUGAAGUGUAGACAAAUGUACUGAGGCUGGAGCCUGUGUGAACAGAACAGAAGAGGCCUUCACUCUAGUAGUGCUCACAGUCCAGCAGCAGGUGUUUGCUGAAGACAGCUUACUCAGAUCACUACUGCCUGGAGGUGGUUGAUAUAUCCUGGUGUAAACCUUCAAGAAGGGCACAGGCAGGAAAACAUGAGCCAGCAACUGAAGAAACGGGCAAAGACAAGACACCAGAAAGGCCUGGGUGGAAGAGCCCCCAGUGGGGCUAAGCCCAGGCAAGGCAAGUCAAGCCAAGACCUGCAGGCGGAAAUAGAACCUGUCAGCGCGGUGUGGGCCUUAUGUGAUGGCUAUGUGUGCUAUGAGCCUGGCCCUCAGGCUCUCGGAGGGGAUGAUUUCUCAGACUGUUACAUAGAAUGCGUCAUAAGGGGUGAGUUUUCUCAACCCAUCCUGGAAGAGGACUCACUUUUUGAGUCCUUGGAAUACCUAAAGAAAGGAUCAGAACAACAGCUUUCUCAAAAGGUUUUCGAAGCAAGCUCCCUUGAAUGUUCUUUGGAAUACAUGAAAAAAGGGGUAAAGAAAGAGCUUCCACAAAAGAUAGUUGGAGAGAAUUCGCUUGAGUAUUCUGAGUACAUGACAGGCAAGAAGCUUCCGCCUGGAGGAAUACCUGGCAUUGACCUAUCAGAUCCUAAACAGCUCGCAGAAUUUGCUAGAAAGAAGCCCCCCAUAAAUAAAGAAUAUGACAGUCUGAGCGCAAUCGCUUGUCCUCAGAGUGGAUGCACUAGGAAGUUGAGGAAUAGAGCUGCCCUGAGAAAGCAUCUCCUCAUUCAUGGUCCCCGAGACCACGUCUGUGCGGAAUGUGGGAAAGCGUUCGUUGAGAGCUCAAAACUAAAGAGACAUUUCCUGGUUCAUACUGGAGAGAAGCCGUUUCGGUGCACUUUUGAAGGGUGCGGAAAGCGCUUCUCUCUGGACUUUAAUUUGCGUACGCACGUGCGCAUCCACACGGGGGAGAAACGUUUCGUGUGUCCCUUUCAAGGCUGCAACAGGAGGUUUAUUCAGUCAAAUAACCUGAAAGCCCACAUCCUAACGCAUGCAAAUACGAACAAGAAUGAACAAGAGGGAAAGUAGUCCUCCAACAGGAUGAAGCAGAUUAACAGAAGAGUGAUCAGUGACAAACAUGCCUCAUUGAUUAUUGUUUCUAGGAAGGAAUUUCUAAAUCAAUAUUGCAACCCCAAAAGCGGUUAUAAUUUGGUGUUACUAAGAUGCUCCUACACUUUGUGAUACCGUUUUAAGGACAUGGUGCAUUUUUUUUUCUUUUAUUUGUUUUAUUUAGAACUUUUUUUAUUUGUUUUAUUUAGAACUUUGUGUGUUCUUAAAGUGUGCUUCCAACAGGAAGGUCAGUGAUAAAUUUUCAAAAGCAUAACCUUCAAUAUAUUAUCUGUUGGAUUAUUGGAUAUAAGACUUAUUUUCAUGUACUAUAAAUAUGAAAAUAACUUUGAUUUUUAAUUGUGUAGUUUCCAUUUCUUAGCUUUUGCCUUUUAAAUUUAUACUUCAGCCAGGCAUAGUGACUGAUGCCUGUAAUCCCAACACUUUGUUGGGAGGCCAAAGCAGGAGGAUAGCUUGAGGCCAGGAGUUCCAGACCAGCCUGGGCAACAUAGUGAGAUCCUGUCUCUACAAAAAAAUUUGUUUUUAUUUGUAUUUAUAUAUUUUUAUUUUUGUUUUUGUUGGUAGGCGUCUCGCUCUGUCACCCAGGCUGGAGUCUAGUGUCGUGAUCUUGGCUCACUGCAACCUCCACCUCCCGGGUUCAAGUGAUUCUCUGGCCUCAGCCUCCCAAGUAGCUGGGACUACAGGUGUGUGUCACCACGCCCGGCUAAUUUUUGUAUUUUUAGUAGAGAUGGGGUUUCACCAUGUUGGCCAGGCUAGUCUCAAACUCCUGACCUCCAGUGAUCUGCCCACCUCGGCCUCCCAAAGUGCUGGGAUUACAGGUGUGAGCCACUGUGCCUGGCCCCCCACAACAUGUUUAAACUUAGCUAGGCCUGGUUGCAUACGCCUGUGUUCCCAGCUACUCAGGAGGCUGAAGCAGGAGGAUAGCUUGAGCCCAGGAGUUUGAGGCUACAGUGAGCUGUGAUUGCACCACUGUACUCCAGACUGGAUAACAGCAAGAGCCCAUCUUUUAAAAAAAGUAAAAAUUAAAAAUAUACUUCAUGGUUCAUGUCAUAGCCCUAGAGAAUGAAAAAUUUGCAGUAGAUAGUCAAUAAAUGAAUCAGUAGUUAAAUAUUCCUUAAAGUCAACUGUAUUUCAUUGUGAUUUUUGUUUUCUUUUUAUCAUUGUAUCAAACUAUAUGGAAAUCAUAUGGUUAGAUGUGAUUAUUUGAUAAUGUUAGUCCAUUUGAAUCCAUUUUAGAUAUUUCACAAUUAAAGAAUAUGAAACUUCAGAAAUAUGCCAAGUCUGUAUUUUAAAAAAUCAAAGUCUACAUUGAAAAGAGAUACCAUUUAUUUGUUCUUAAAACUUAGCAAAAUUCAACAGACUGAUGUUCGGUAUAGGUGAGAUAUGGCGGGAAGUUGGGCUUACGUGUGGUUGGAUAAGGGAUAAACUGUCACAGCCAGUUUGGAAAUAAAUUUUGUAAUUGUGCUA